UUUUUUUUUUUUUUUUAAUAAAGACAGAGUCUUGCUCUGUUGUCCAGGCUGGCAUGCAGUGGCGUGAUCACGGCUUACUGCAGCUUUGACCUCCUGAGCUCAAGUGAUCCUCCCACUUCUGCCUCCCAAGUAGCUGGGACCACAGAUGUGUACCACCAUGCCUUGCUAAUUUUAAAAUUUUUUAAUAGAGAUGGGGGUCUGUCUGUGUUGCCCAGACUGGUCUCAAGUGAUUCUCCCACCUCAGCCUCCCAAAGUAUUGGGAUUGCAGGCAUGACUCACAGCGCCUGGCCUCAGUUUCUUUCAAGACCAUCCUAUAACACCAAGUUAGUUUGAGGAUUCUAUGAAUGUCUGCUUAAAGAUAUCCUUCUGAAUUCUGUGAUUCUCUUGAAAGGCUUGUUGCAAUGAAAAACAAAGUAUAAUGAUGACUUUAUGUGAAGUAUACUUUUGGAAUUUCUUAAGCAGAAGUCCUGAGACUUUUGAGAGUCCCUGUAUUUAAACAGUACCAUUUAGGCACAGUUACUGCUUAUGAAAUGAAGAGUAGCUAGAUGAAUAUAAAAAAUCUUACUCUUACAUUUCAACCCAGCAUUAUUUGAACCCAGCAAAAUUAUUUCUAUAGUAGAAUCAAUUUAGUUCCUUAUUUUAAGCCAUGCAUAUAUAUCUCAAAGCAAAUUUCAAGAGGGAUUAAAUGUUAUUAUGUGAAAAUAUUAGGAGGUGAAAUAAUAGGAGAAAGUAAACACAUUGAAAGUAGGUAUGUUCAGGCCAGGCGCGGUGGCUUAUGCCUGUAAUCCCAGCACUUUGGGAGGCUGAGGCGGGCAGAUCACGAGGUCAGGAGAUCGAGACCAUCCUGGCUAACACGGUGAAACCCCGUCUCUACUAAAAAUACAAAAAAAAAUUAGCCGGGCGUGGUGGCGGGCAUUUGUGGUCCCAGCUACUCGGGAGGCUGAGGCAGGAGAAUCGAUUUAACCCUGGAGGCUGAGGUUGCAGUGAGCCGAGAUUGCACCACUGCACCCUAGCCUGGCAACAGAGCAAGACUCUGUCUCAAAAAAAAAAAAGGAAAGUAGGUAUGUUUACAAUUUAAAAUCUUUGGGCAUGGAGAUAAGCUAUAAGGCCAUUGAUCAGAAUGGACCAUUUCAUAAUGUUCCAAAAAUUAGACUACUUUGGAAAAAGGUGGUGUGUGGUCUUAAUGUAGGCAAUGCACAUGUGUGUUUAAGUUUCAAAUACAGCUAAGGAGCUAAGUGGAAUUUUUUUUUUUUUUUUUUACCAAAUAGCGUGUAUUAAUAAUAGCUCAGUUCCAUUUACUGAUUUGUUUUUCCUUUGUUUAUGUCAUAUAUUAUCUUUCCAAGAGAUUGUGAGUUUAUGCUACUGCCAAUUUGGUAUGAGGGCCUGUUUUUAAAAGAGCUGCAUGAUAUUCACUUGGAUGUACCACGAUUUAUUCAACCAGUCUUUUCUUUGUCAUUAGACAUUUAGUUUAUUUAAAGCCUUUCAACAUUAUAAGUAACUGUGAAAGAUAUCUUUGUGCUAUGAGUUGCCUACAUUUUGGAUCAUUGCCACUAAGAAAGAAAUUAACUAGUGACUCAAUUAUUCCUUGCUUUUUUUGAGCAAAAAUCAUAUUAAAAAUAAUUAGAUUUAAAAUUUUUGGUUAAAUUAUACUUUAAAGCAAAGAUCCUUGCCAUUUAGAUCUAGUUUGGUAUUAAAUGAGAACGGUGGUUCUCUACUGUGUUGGUGGGGGAUAUGUUCAUGAUGGAUUUUGCUGUGGAAGGACAUUUGGCAAUGCCUGGAGAGAGUUUUGGUUGUUACAGAUGCAGGGAGGGGUGCCACUGACAUCUAAUGGGUAGAGGCCAGGGAUGCUGCUGCUAAACAUCCUGCAAUACACAAGACAGUCCCCACUUGCCCCCCCCCCCCCAAAAAAAAUUAGCUAGCCUAAAAUGUCAGUAGUGCUGAGGCUGAGAAACCUUGGAUUAACAGGUUUCACUGCUGAUGGGAAACUUUUUUUUUUUUAACAGGGCCUUACUCUGUUGCCCAGGCUAGAGUGCAGUAGCAGGAUGCUAGCUCACUGCAGUCUUGAACUCCUGAGUUCAAGCAAUCCUCCUGUCUCUGCCUCCCAAGAAGCUGGAACUACACAUGCACACCACCAUCCCCAGCUAAUUAAAAAAAUUUUUUGGCAGAGCUGGUGUCUUACUGUGUUGCCCAGGCUGGUCUCAAACUCCUACCCUCAAGUGAUCCUUCCAGCUGGGCCUCCCAAAGCACCAGGAUUGCAGGAAUGUGCAUUUUACCUUGCUGUCACAGGAUGGCUCCUGCCUGUUCCCACCCCUCACCCCCGGCAGCAAAACCUAUGUUCCAGGCAGGCAGCAGUGAGGACAAAGGAAAUUCGAAAUGAGUCCCAUGACUAUCCUCAUAGAGUGGCCAAGUUUCCAGAAAACAGAAAUCGAAACAGAUACAGAGAUGUAAGCCCAUAUGAUCACAGUCGUGUUAAACUGCAAAAUGCUGAGAAUGAUUAUAUUAAUGCCAGUUUAGUUGACAUAGAAGAGGCACAAAGGAGUUACAUCUUAACACAGGGUCCACUUCCUAACACAUGCUGCCAUUUCUGGCUUAUGGUUUGGCAGCAGAAGACCAAAGCAGUUGUCAUGCUGAACCGCAUUGUGGAGAAAGAAUCGGUUAAAUGUGCACAGUACUGGCCAACAGAUGACCAAGAGAUGCUGUUUAAAGAAACAGGAUUCAGUGUGAAGCUCUUGUCAGAAGAUGUGAAGUCGUAUUAUACAGUACAUCUACUACAAUUAGAAAAUAUCAAUAGUGGUGAAACCAGAACAAUAUCUCACUUUCAUUAUACUACCUGGCCAGAUUUUGGAGUCCCUGAAUCACCAGCUUCAUUUCUCAAUUUCUUGUUUAAAGUGAGAGAAUCUGGCUCCUUGAACCCUGACCAUGGGCCUGCGGUGAUCCACUGUAGUGCAGGCAUUGGGCGCUCUGGCACCUUCUCUCUGGUAGACACUUGUCUUGUUUUGAUGGAAAAAGGAGAUGAUAUUAACAUAAAACAAGUGUUACUGAACAUGAGAAAAUACCGAAUGGGUCUUAUUCAGACCCCAGAUCAACUGAGAUUCUCAUACAUGGCUAUAAUAGAAGGAGCAAAAUGUAUAAAGGGAGAUUCUAGUAUACAGAAACGAUGGAAAGAACUUUCUAAGGAAGACUUAUCUCCUGCCUUUGAUCAUUCACCAAACAAAAUAAUGACUGAAAAAUACAAUGGGAACAGAAUAGGUCUAGAAGAAGAAAAACUGACAGGUGACCGAUGUACAGGACUUUCCUCUAAAAUGCAAGAUACAAUGGAGGAGAACAGUGAGAGUGCUCUACGGAAACGUAUUCGAGAGGACAGAAAGGCCACCACAGCUCAGAAGGUGCAGCAGAUGAAACAGAGGCUAAAUGAGAAUGAACGAAAAAGAAAAAGGCCAAGAUUGACAGACACCUAAUAUUCAUGACUUGAGAAUAUUCUGCAGCUAUAAAUUUUGAACCAUUGAUGUGCAAAGCAAGACCUGAAGCCCACUCCGGAAACUAAAGUGAGGCUCGCUAACCCUCUAGAUUGCCUCACAGUUGUUUGUUUACAAAGUAAACUUUACAUCCAGGGGAUGAAGAGCACCCACCAGCAGAAGACUUUGCAGAACCUUUAAUUGGAUGUGUUAAGUGUUUUUAAUGAGUGUAUGAAAUGUAGAAAGAUGUACAAGAAAUAAAUUAGGGGAGAUUACUUUGUAUUGUACUGCCAUUCCUACUGUAUUUUUAUACUUUUUGGCAGCAUUAAAUAUUUUUGUUAAAUAGUC